AGUCCUUUCUGUGUUUAUUCCCAUCUCUCCCAAAUAUUUGGAAACUGAUGUCUUGACUCAUGGGUGUAUUCACAAAUUCUGUUACUUCAAGUCUUUUUCUUUUAACGGAUUGAUCUUUUGCUAGAUAGAGACAAAAUAUCAGUGUGAAUUACAGCAAACCCCUAUUCCAUGCUGUUAUGGGUGAAACUCUGGGAGAUUCUCCUAUUGACCCAGAAAGCGAUUCCUUCACUGAUACACUGUCUGCAAACAUAUCACAAGAAAUGACCAUGGUUGACACAGAGAUGCCAUUCUGGCCCACCAACUUUGGGAUCAGCUCCGUGGAUCUCUCCGUAAUGGAAGACCACUCCCACUCCUUUGAUAUCAAGCCCUUCACUACUGUUGACUUCUCCAGCAUUUCUACUCCACAUUACGAAGACAUUCCAUUCACAAGAACAGAUCCAGUGGUUGCAGAUUACAAGUAUGACCUGAAACUUCAAGAGUACCAAAGUGCAAUCAAAGUGGAGCCUGCAUCUCCACCUUAUUAUUCUGAGAAGACUCAGCUCUACAAUAAGCCUCAUGAAGAGCCUUCCAACUCCCUCAUGGCAAUUGAAUGUCGUGUCUGUGGAGAUAAAGCUUCUGGAUUUCACUAUGGAGUUCAUGCUUGUGAAGGAUGCAAGGGUUUCUUCCGGAGAACAAUCAGAUUGAAGCUUAUCUAUGACAGAUGUGAUCUUAACUGUCGGAUCCACAAAAAAAGUAGAAAUAAAUGUCAGUACUGUCGGUUUCAGAAAUGCCUUGCAGUGGGGAUGUCUCAUAAUGCCAUCAGGUUUGGGCGGAUGCCACAGGCCGAGAAGGAGAAGCUGUUGGCGGAGAUCUCCAGUGAUAUCGACCAGCUGAAUCCAGAGUCCGCUGACCUCCGGGCCCUGGCAAAACAUUUGUAUGACUCAUACAUAAAGUCCUUCCCGCUGACCAAAGCAAAGGCGAGGGCGAUCUUGACAGGAAAGACAACAGACAAAUCAGUUAGUUCUCUUCUGCUGUCUUCAUUGGGGGAGGCGGGAAGUUGUUUUGGGUUUUUGUUUCUUUGAGUAAAUGGUUUACUGCGCUACAAAUGCACACACAGAAUAUUGUUCAACUGUUGGCUGUUAACAUAUUGCAGGCUGAGUCUGAAACGCAGGAAGUGUUUUCAGAUAGCACAAGUCAACAUUAUUUUGAAAAGGGAGAAAAGUCCAUAAAGUUUUUGAGAAUAGUGUAACAAUGUAUUGGUCAUCCUAACUUUAAUGAAUGAACUUAAGCCCCCUGAGCCUAUCACCCUCUUUUAGGAUCCAUCUCCUUUCUCGGCAUCAAAAUAACUGGCCACAGCAAUAUUCAUUCAAGCAGCCUUGCUUUCCUCUGGGAAGAACCCGACCUAGGUUUAGAAAAGGUAUUGAAUCCCACUAUUUCACCUUUCAGGAGAACUACCAGAGUUACCUCUUUUUUUUUUUUUUUUUUUUUUUUUGAGAUGUCGUCUCACUUUGUCGCCCAGGCUGGAGUGCAGUGGCACAAUCUCGGCUCACCGCAACCUCCGCCUCCCAGGUUAAAGCGAUUAUCAUGCCUCAGCAUCCCGAGUAGCUGGGAUUACAGGUGUGCACGACCAUGCCUGGCUAAUCUUUGUAUUUUUAGUAGAGACGGGGUUUCACCUUGUUGAUCAGGCUGGUCUAGAGUUACCUCUUAAGAAGUUCAACAUGAGGCAUAAAAAUAGAUUCUAGAUAUUAUGUUACCUUUCUUUCCUUGUAGCAUUCUUGAUUAUUCCGGGGCAACUAGAAGCUCUAUCCUUUUAUUACAUAUGUGAAUUUUAUCUUCUGCAAGGCUCUGAGCUGCCUGGACUACUUCAGUGGACUCUCCAACAUCUGUUCACUCAUUGAGCAGCACUGUUUAGAAAACCCAGAAUGGGUUGUAAUUGUUACUGAGUUAGGUUUUCCAAGCAGCAGAGCUCUUCUCUGACUGGAAACUGAGAAAACAACAUGGAAUUAUAGAAUAAAAUUGUACCUGAAUUCUAGUCCCAAUUCUGCCAUCAGCUUGGAUGACCUGGAUCAUGUCUCUGUACCUCAGUUUGUUGUUGUUGUUGUUGUUGUUGUUUUGAGACAGAGUCUUGCUCUGUUGCCAGGCUGGAAUGCAGUGGCGUGAUCUCGGCUCACUGCAACCUCCACCUCCCUGGUUCAAGCAAUUCUCCUGCGUCAGCCUCCCGAGUAGCUGGGAUUGCAGGCGCAUGCCACCAUGCCCAGCUAAUUUUUUUGUAUUUUUAGUAGAGAUGGGUUUUCACCAUGUUGGCCAGGAUGGUCUUGAUCUCCUGACCUCGUGAUCUGCCCGCCUCUGCCUCCCAAAGUGCUGGGAUUACAGGCAUGAGCCACCGCGCCCGGCUUUGUAGCUCAGUUUUUAAUGACAGGGUUUGGCUUUGAUUCUGAUGUCUGCACAACGCUCCCAGGGCUGUAAGAACUGCAGAACACACUGAGAAGACACCGUCCCAGCCAUGGAAAGCCCUUCUAUGCAGUCAUUUAUUUUCACAUGAACACCUCCCAGAGAGCUAUGCAAUGACUUGAUAGAUAUGUGUAACUUUUCCCCUAUUCAGAUAUAUUGUUAGGAAAAUCUCAUUAACCUUUCAUGUAUUUUGAUGACUAUCUCAAGAUGGUAGUUCUUCUGUUUAGCUAAACUAGUAAGAGUAGAAUCAGUUAAUAGAAAAAGGAAACUUAUGGCAUAAAGCCAUAUGGUAAUAAGGACAAUGAGUUUUCUGAUUUGAAAAUAGGUCUUUGAUACCUCAACAAUAAUAUACCUGGAUUCAAUUCUUUACAGUAUAAAAAAAACCUUGCACAUUUGUUAGGUUCGAGCCACAUGCACCUGACUACUGCUAUUAUUAUCCUCUUUAUUUUAGAGAUGAGGAAAAUAAAGUCCAGAGAGGUUAAACAUUUUGCCCUAAGACCCCACAGCAAGUGGGUAGAAGACCUGGGACUAUAAUGCAGGUUUUCUGGCCUCUAGUUCAGAGCAUUCGUAGCAUGCUAGCCCCUCAGUAGCAUAGUACUUUAGGAAGCUAGUCUUUCCCACUUGCUGGUAGUAAGCCAGGGAGACAUAAUACACUAAGAAAGCUUCGGUCUGAGAAAACUUUCCAUGAUUGUUUUUUCUCAAUUUUUAGAACAGUAGGAAUUCUUCACCUCAUCUGCUAUCCCAACAUAUUCACAAUUGGAAAAUUUUUGUGCUGUUCUGUUCUUUUCAAAUUACAAAAGUCCUUGACUAGGACUGCUGGCUUUUACAUGCACAGGACUGCACAACACUGGUGUUUAUAAAGCUCAUUCGUUCAAUGAUAAAAUUGGCCAUAGCAAAUCAAAAAUAAAUGAAGACCUCUGCGUAGCUGAUUGGACUACAGAAAAUAAGCCAUUCAUAUCCAGGAAGAAAAAAUUAAAAGGAUUGCUGAAAAGGAAAGAGCCCUAAAGCAAACUAUCUACAGUUUUGGUUAGUUUUCUUUUCUUUUCUUUUCUUUUUUUUUUUUUUUUUUUGAGGUGGGGUCUUGCUUUGUUGCCCAGGUGGGAGUGUCUUCUUAUAUUGGUCAGGCUGGCCUUGAACUCGGGGCUCAAGCCGUCCUCCCACCUCAGCCUCCCAAAGAGCUGGUAUUACAGGUGUGAGCCACCAGCCAUGGUUAGUUUUCAUCAACUGCUUUCUCACCUUCUUUUCAUCCUCUAAUUCAUACCUGCAAUCCUUAUUAGAAAUCCUGUCAACUUAAUAGUACCAGAAAGUCAGGCAAAAGACUGAUAAAAAAAAAGCCUCGGUGGUCAAGAACUUAAAAUUACACUACUGGUGUGCAACGUGCUCUUAUCUGUGUUACUGGAGGACACCCUCAAGAUACCUCACUCCAGUUGACUCCUUGGCUCUAAAUCUUUGAGUUAAAAAAUAAGGAGGUUCUUUAUGGAAUAAACAGGUAUUAAGCUAUUUAAAGGAGAGGGCUGCGAAAUGCUUGAUUAUGGGCUUUUCAAGUUCAGAGGCCAAGCGUUUGUCAUUUUCUUCCAGUAACUAGGACUGUGUCUUGCCCCUAAUAGUUACUCAGACUAUAUUUGCUUAAUUGAAUUAAACACAGUUGCCUAUGCCCUUUGAAAUUCUGGACUUUCAACAGAGGGCCUCUAGCCCAAUAUUUGCUUACCAAACUGGACAUCAUUGAUGAUCUGGAUUCAGGCAGGGUCUGGAAAAAGAGAGACUGGGCCAAAUUAAAAUAAUCCAUUCACUGAUGACACAAAACUAAACUACAAUUGUUUGGCACCCUCUCUUCUCCUUAUCUUGCAAAAUCAAAUUAAGCACUAGUGGAAAGAAACAGUUCAGAGAGGAAUAUGGGAAAGGAAAAAAAAAAACCAAAAUGUGAUUUCCAACGAGACUAGAGAUUUGUUCUUUAUCUACAUGGUCAUGUUACUCAUUUGAUAGCAUCUAUCUCAGGGGUAUUAUGUUAUCUCUUGGCCAGGACUCAUGAAAGUUAAGAUUUGCAUUGAUAGGAAAAGUUUUGCAGAAAUAUGGACUCUUGAGAGGGUGGGAGGUAUAUAAAAGUGGCUAUGGCUGUGCAGCAGAGCAAUUUGCAUUUCUUAUACACCCUGCUUGAGACUGAUGUCAUUAGUGUUGGUUAGGCCAAGGCUGGGGGAGGCUACUCAGAAUAGUGGGUGACCAAUUACCCAGAACCUUUGGAAAAGGAAAUGACUUGAUUGAAGAGGCCAUUCUUUAAAUGUAUCUUACUGCUCAAUUUCACCAUUGCCUAUUGUAGAAUGCGCCCUGCCCGCUCAGCAUUUGCCUCUAGGCAGACCAGGACUCCUUCCCCUCCCCAACUAAUCUUCCUUCUCCUGUAUCUUAUUCCCUAGGGCCACUUGCACCUUUCAAAAUGGAUAAAUUAAAUUCCCCUGCUCCCCUUCUACCAACUUUAACAUCAUAUCCUUGGUGUAUGAUGCCCUACUUUUCAUUGUUUUGCCUAAAUAAGAGUAUGCUUGGGAAUUUUAGGCUUAGGGCUGGGAAAAGAUGGGAUAUGGAAUCGUCAGCUAUAGAUUGCCGGACAAGAAAUUUUAGGAGCAGUAGACCUUUCAACCGCCCUCAAUAGGAUGGAACUGACUGUCCCCACAACCUAUUUCCCUUUCAGUGGCUUGCUCCAGCCAAGGCCCCUUAUUUAAGAGAUCUUUGUGCGCUCUGAAAACCAUGCAUAUGCCAGAACUAGGUGCUCUGUUUCAUGAAGGCAGUUUGAUAACUGAAUGGACUUUGGAAGUGCCCAGUGUUUGACUAUUACCCUGGUGCGAUGAUCACACUGGGCGUAUCAUUGUCACAUGAUCCCAUGUUUGUUGAUGAAAAUAAACAGUGGUUUUCAAAAACCA